GCCCCCGCCCAGGUGUCUCCCUUUGGGAAGCUGCCCGCCGAGUCUCCGAGAUUUGUCCCUGGUGGUCCCGCGGACCCCUCGUCCCUCCGCAGUCUCCGGCUGGCAGCGAUGGAGGGCGCUGGGGAGAACGCCCCGGAGUCCAGCUCCUCUGCCCCUGGGUCCGAAGAGUCUGCCAGGGAUCCACAGGUGCCGCCUCCGGAGGAAGAAUCGGGGGACUGCGCCCGGUCCCUGGAGGCGGUCCCCAAGAAACUCUGUGGGUAUUUAAGUAAGUUCGGCGGCAAAGGGCCCAUCCGGGGCUGGAAAUCCCGCUGGUUCUUCUACGACGAAAGGAAAUGUCAGCUGUAUUACUCGCGGACCGCUCAGGAUGCCAAUCCCUUGGACAGCAUCGACCUCUCCAGUGCAGUGUUUGACUGUAAGGCGGACGCUGAGGAGGGGAUCUUCGAAAUCAAGACUCCCAGCCGGGUUAUUACCCUGAAGGCCGCCACCAAGCAAGCGAUGCUGUACUGGCUGCAGCAGCUGCAGAUGAAGCGCUGGGAAUUCCACAACAGCCCGCCGGCACCUCCUGCCACCCCUGAUGCCGCCCUGGCUGGGAAUGGGCCCGUCCUGCACCUCGAGCUAGGGCAAGAAGAGGCAGAGCUGGAGGAGUUCCUGUGCCCUGUGAAAACACCCCCUGGGCUAGUGGGCGUGGCAGCUGCCUUGCAGCCCUUCCCUGCCCUUCAGAAUAUUUCCCUCAAGCACCUGGGGACUGAAAUACAGAACACAAUGCACAACAUCCGUGGCAACAAGCAGGCCCAGGGAACAGGCCAUGAACCUCCAGGGGAAGAUUCUCCACAGAGUGGGGAGCCUCAGAGGGAGGAGCAGCCCUUGGCCUCUGACGCCAGCACCCCAGGGAGAGAGCCAGAGGAUUCUCCAAAGCCUGCACCCAAGCCUUCUCUGACCAUCAGUUUCGCUCAGAAAGCCAAGCGCCAGAACAACACCUUCCCAUUCUUUUCUGAAGGAAUCACACGGAACCGAACUGCCCAGGAGAAAGUGGCAGCCUUGGAGCAACAGGUUCUGAUGCUCACCAAGGAGUUAAAGUCUCAGAAGGAGCUAGUGAAGAUCCUGCACAAGGCACUGGAGGCCGCCCAGCAGGAGAAGCGGGCGUCCAGCGCAUACCUGGCGGCGGCUGAGGACAAGGACCGGCUGGAGCUGGUGCGGCACAAAGUGCGGCAGAUCGCGGAGCUGGGCCGGCGGGUGGAGGCCCUGGAGCAGGAGCGGGAGAGCCUGGCGCACACAGCGAGCCUGCGGGAGCAGCAGGUGCAGGAGCUACAGCAGCACGUGCAGCUGCUUAUGGACAAGAACCACGCCAAGCAGCAGGUCAUCUGCAAGCUCUCUGAGAAGGUCACCCAGGACUUCACGCACCCCCCUGACCAGUCUCCUUUGCGCCCCGACGCUGCCAACAGGGACUUCCUGAGCCAGCAGGGGAAGAUAGAGCACCUGAAGAUGUGGAAUGCUGAGGCUGAGAAAGGUUAAGGAGCCUGCCCAGGGUCAUGUGCUGAAGAAGUGGAGGAGCUGGAGCUGGGCUGGAGCUCAUGUCUGCGGUCUGGUCUGUCUGCUCAGCUGCCGCUUCUAGCUGCUGCCACCAUCCCUGCUCCUCCUUUCCUCCCCUUCCUUCCCCUUCUCUGUCCCUAUCUUUCCCUAGGCUUCCCCACCCCACAGGGACCAGUGAUGUCACAGGAGGUAGGAACUUUAUGUGAAGUGUGUUGCCUGCCGUGACCCGCAGCCUCCUCUCUAAAGGGUUGUGACAGGAACUGUCCCACUGGGAGGCCUGUGGCUGUGGAGUGCACUCAUAGCCUCCACUGUCCGUAAAGGGAGCCAUACAACCAGAGUUCGUCCUGCCCCAAACCCUGCCACUCACAACCACAUAUGUACAGUCAGAUGCCAUAUAACAGGCUGCAUAUGUGAUGGUCCCAUAAGAUUACAAUGAAGCAGAAAAAUCCCUGUCACAUAGUGACAUCAUAGCCGUCAUAACAUCAUAGCACAACAUGCUACCUUUUCUAUGUUUACAUGUGUUUAGAUACACAAAUGCCAUUAUGUGACAGCCACCUAUGGUAUUCAGUACCGUAACAGGUGCACAGGUCUGCAGCCUCGGAGCAAUAGGCUACACCAUCUAGCUGGGUGCGUAGUAGGCUAAAUCACCUAGGUUUGUCUGCGUCCAGUCUACAAUGUUUGCACAACAGUGAAAUCACCUAAUGACGCAUUUCUCAGAGUGUAUCCUCAUAAUUAAGCCACACGAGACUGUACAUAUAGACUUAUAACCUUGAGAACUCUCAUGCUACUCUAUCAAAGAACUACUCGGUGAGGGCAGAUGGAGAAAGAAAAAAAAAGAAAUCAGGAAGCUUUUGAGAGAAAAGCUCUCAGUGGGCAGUGUUGAACAGUGGCCACCACCCAAGCUUUGAAGUCAGACUGACCUCUUUGACUCUUGGCUCUGCCUCUUUCUGGCUGUGUGACUUUAGGCAUGUUAGCUCACCUCUGUGUCAAAUAGCCCAACUAGUCCUCUUGACUAGGGCUGUUAGAAGGAUAAAGGAAAAGGACGUGAAACCUGAUUCCCUUCCCUUUCUUUCAGCAAAGACUGAAAACCCACAUAACCAGUUCCCGAAUCUUUUCCCUUAUUUAGUCUGAAAUCAGAGAUUCUUUUGGGUUAAAAGAAAAACAUAACCUUUCCAAUGCAAAUGCAGCCAGAUGAUUAGAAAGCUCUCAGCCCUCCACACAGCAGGGAAAACUGCUUCCAUCUGAUUGCUUUUCUACCCUGCCUGCCCCCAGCCAGGCGGCUUCCUCUUCUCUCCACCCAUACUGCCGGAAUCCACUGUGCAAGCCCCGGUAGAGCAGCACAGGGGUCAGAAAGAUUUGUGGUGGCGCACGCCUGUGUUCCCGUCUACUCUGGAGGCCGAGGUGGGAGGAUCGCUUGAGCCCACGAGGUGGAGGUUGCAGUGAGCUGAGAUUGUGCCACUGCACUCCAACCUGGGUGAAGGAGUGAAACACCAUCUCAAAGGAAAAAAAAGAACACUAGAUCAGCCAGGUGGCUCCAGACAGCCUGAGAGUUGAUUGUAAUCAUGGACUCACUAGGAGACUGAGUGUGCCCCUGAAUUUACAUAUUCAGGAAUUUUAUUUUUUUUUAUUUUUAUUUUUUGAGACGGAGUCUUGCUCUGUCACCCAGCCUGGAGUGCAGUGGCGCGGUCUCGGCUCACUGCAAGCUCCGCCUCCCAGGUUCACGCCAUUCUCCUGCCUCAGCCUCCUGAGUAGCUGGGACUACAGGUGCCCGCCACCAUGCCCGGCUAAUUUUUUUGUAUUUUUAGUAGAGACGGGGUUUCACCAUGUUAGCCAGGAUGGUCUUGAUCUCCUGACCGCGUGAUCUGCCUGCCUCGGCCUCCCAAAGUGCUGGGAUUACAGGUGUGAGCCACCGCACCUGGCCAUGAAUUUUCUUUAUCAGUGAGCUCAGCUACAUGGAGACUCUGGGUAUGUGAUUCACAUUAACCAAGAAUACACUUGCAUAUGAUCCUCAGAGGCCCAGUGUUUUGUGCUUUGUGCUUUAAAGGGUUGCAUAAGGCCAGGCAUGGGUGGCUCACACCUGUAAUGCCAGCAUUUGGGGAGGCUGUGGCAGGAGGAUUACUUGAGGCCAGGAGUUAGAGACAAGCCGGGGAAACAUAGCAAGAUCUCAUCUCUACAAAAAAUUAAAAAAUUAGCCAGGCACAGUAGCACGUGCCUGUAGUCCCAGCUACUUGGGAAGCUGAAGCUAGAGGAUUGCUUAAGCCCAGGAGUUCAUGACCAGCCUAGGCAACAUAGCAAGACCCUGUCUCUAAAAAAAAAUAAAAUAAAUUCACUAGGUAUGAAGGCACCCGCCAUAGUCCUAGCUACUCAGAAGGCUGAGGUGGGAGAUUACUUGAGCCGCCCAGGAGUUCGAGGCUGUGGUGAACUGUGAUCACGCCACUGCACUCCAGCCUGGACAACAGAGUAAGACACUGUCUCUAUUAAAAAAAAAAUAAAAAAGAGAAAGAGUUGCAUGUAGUUGGUGUUCCUUAGUUUUUAGCUUUUAGAAUACCCAUCAAAUAUCCAUUGUCUUGAGUUUGAGGACAGAGAAUGUUGAGGUUUCCUGCCUGCCCUGUGAUUGAGGAACCCAACUUUAGGGAAUGCCCCUUGUUAUUCAGACUUUGGUUUUGAGAACAGGAUCACUGACCUCUUGAAUAUCAGAUCUGGAAAGACUCAGAAAUCUAGUCUGCCCCACUCAUUUUCUGGCAGGGACAGCUGAGCUGGGGCAAGGGAGAAGGACUGGCCCAGGGUCAGGCAGCAAGAGGCAGGGCUACAGCCGGAACCUGGCCUCCCAUGCCCAGGCCACUGCCUUCCACACAGCACAGGGCCUAGUCCAUGGGCAUGGCCCAAAGAGAAUUCCCGGGCUCCUGCUUCCCUGGUCCCCCUUCUCCAGGGUUUUCCUUCUUUCAUUCCACUGGUGACUGUCCUGUGGCUUUUCUCUUUUCUGAGGUUUCUCUUUUUCCUCC